CAGAACCCAAGGGCUUACCUGUGCUCUGUGAUUCCCCAACUAGGGAUUUAGUUGUAGCCACGGACCUGGUAGGCAACAGGGAGGGGAUUUUAAUCUGCUCCUUGCAUCAGAAGGUCCAAUAGGCAGGGUUAGUAUAAUGGGAGAUGCCCUGGUAGGGCUGGCAAGGAGAAGAAGCCACAUGUAUUUUGGUCUGAUGAAAAGCAGCAGUGAUCUGUCACUGACCAAAAUGGUCCCCCAACUAUGCAUUACGGAGCAGCAACCCACAUACAGAACUCGAGAAGCCACGGCCUGGAGACUGUACCUGGACACCAAAGACUGGAGAGAGGAGCUGGUGGGGAAACCCCAGAGUUCCCAGGGUGCCACUCCCCAGCUCCACCAGAGAACUUUGGGAAUGAGCUGCUGCCCCUGAGUGCCCCUCUCCAGGGCCUCAGUGAGGGUCUCUACCCUCCAGGGAGGAACAAAACCUUGCCAGCUGGGGUCCUGCGAGAGGGGGCAGUUCAAUUCCUCCACAGGGGACUCUGCAACUCCAAUCUUUCGAGUGAAGCAUCUGCGAGGCCCUCAGGGACCCAGGAUGAACUGCAUAGCAGCAGAAGGAAGACAGGCCAGACCAGGCGGGAGGGAGCCCGGAAACAUCUGGUUUGUAGUUUCAGACUCUACCCGUUCACAGUUCACACAGUCUCACCGGGAAACUCACACCUUGCCCUGUACCAAGUUUUUAAGGCAGUUAAGCUCUGCCCAUCCGAGACUUCAUUUUUCUUGAGUAGAAAAUCACUGAAAUCAUCAGAUCCAUGGCACCCACCUUCACUUUCUCCUAACAGCUGGAACCGUCAGGCUGGCUUCAGGGCCUGGUCUUCGCACUUGAUAUCACUAUCCCUCACCUGCUCAGACAGCCAGAGCAGGCGGGUGAGUUCCUCCCAACAACCUCCACUGCAUUCUCUCAGCUCCCACCGCAGGGCAGCCCACGUGCCUGAGUGAACAUGUGUGCGUGUGCACACACGCAAGUAUGCACAGACAUACACUAAACACGAACAUACAGUGCACAUGAACGCUGCUCCCAGCUAGGGCCCUCUGGUCAGACUGCUGCCUGGGUUAGAAUUCUUGUCCCCACCCCCACUUACUAUAGUUCUGUGAUCCUGGACAAGUAACUGAAUCUCUCCGUGCCACAGUUUCUUCUUGUAGAAAACGGGAAAGUUCACAGUACUUACCUCCUUAGAGUCAUUGUGAAGGUCAGUUUGAGGCAUCACAAAUUUAAGGCACCCAGACAUAAGGGUCAACAGGGUUAGCUAUCACUGUCCAGUUUGGUGGGAGGAACUGAAUGCAUGUAGGCACAUGGACCCAGUCUACACUCAGGCACAAAAGGAGCUACAUUAGUUACAUUCAGGCAUACCCCAGAGCACUACAAUUCUCUGAGACAUUGUCUGGAAAUCUAGAAAUCAUCUCCUUGCCCUUUAAGGUAUUUUAACCCUCGCAUUCCUCUGCUUUUCCAAGAAUGUGAAUCUUGCCAAGCUGUCCGUGAGAGACACGGGCUCCCCUCGAGGGAGACUUGCAAAUGCUCCAUAAACAGCCACAGUGUGGGGCUCUGCCAUGAGGAAGUCACAGCAGACACGCUAGACAGCAUAGUCCUGGAUGCAACCUGGAGGAAGGGAGGCCCAUGGUGGAGCACUCACUCCGUGCCUGUCUGCCCGGUGAGACCUCAAGUUCCUUGCAGACAAAGGCCAUGGGUUGUUGGCUCUUGUGUUCCCGGUGGCCUUUCCAGAGCUGAACAGAGGACAGAUGCACAGACGGGGGGGCUCUGGUGGUCAAGGCAGCAGUCCCCUUGGAUACUAAAGUCUGAGCCAGGCCCCUCAGGCCCGGCAUGGGCAGUGCGAGGCCCAUAGUGGUGGGAAGCCAGUUGGCCAGCUGGGGUGAGAAGGCCGCGAAGCCAUGGGCAGACAGGAAGUGGAGGUGAAUGUCUCUGCCUCCUGUAGGCCUCAGCAGGGACAGCACAGACCCUCUGGCUGGGGCAGCGCAGACCCUCUAGCUGGGGCAGAACAAGGCUGGUGCUUCCUUCUAGUCCUUGAGACUUUGUAGCUCUAACUCAAGCAGAACCCUGGGGUUUUGGGAUUCUGUGUGGUGACUGCUGAGGAAGGUUUAUGGAUUUGACAGGGUGCAUGUCACAGAGAGACAGUUCUCAGUCAGCACUUCCUGUCCCCUGCAGAGGCUCAUAGGGGACAGCCCCUGCCAAGGAGACCCUGGAGGGGCUCUGAGGAUAGCAAUCAGAGGUUGGGCUGGCUGGACUGAGCCCAGGCCUGUUGCCCACCAAGUCUCCAUAGGUUCUAGUCUGACCCCUCUCUCCACCCCUGGGCUAUGCAGGCCAGCCCGUGCAGACCACCCCCGACGCGUCCACUUGCAACACCCGCCUCACUGUGCCAACACUCCAUCCACACAGGAAAGGACUGAGAACGUGAUGCUUAACCCAAAGGAGUGAGUUUCAUAGGAUGGGUGGCUUUAACAGUUUCACAGCAGGACACUGAGGGAAUAUUUCCCUAUCCCUUCAAAUGGACGGUCACUACAGAAACGUGUAGAGCAAGACUUUGUCAAGGGGCUGUUUCCAGGUCUCCCGGUGUCUAAAUAGCAGAGCUGGAAUGGGAACUGAGAACCGAUUCUUUCCACAACCGCCCACUGAGCAGCAAGGCUGCAGCCAGCAAAGAGGUGCGGAGGCAAGCAAGCUCCAUGUGGUGGGGACAGCGCAUUGCGACCUCCACCACCCCUGCAGUGGGCUGCCAGCUGAGCCACCUGUCUUCCACUGUAUCUACUGUACGAACUUCUCCAGCUCUGCUCUGUUUUCUCUUCCUCAGCAUCCACCCCGUGACACGUAGUGGUGGCUGAUGUCGCCACAGUACCAUGAGGUUAACAGGUCCUCCCUCCAGCUUCCCUCAUGGUGGCAGCCUAACCUGCAUUGCAGCCGUUCACCGGACACCGCACCAGACCCUCAAAACCCAUCCAAGACUGUGGGAGGAGUAAACAACCCAGCCCAGUUAAGAGGAGAUGCCGAAUUUAAUGAACCCUAUUUGAAUUGCAGGGCUGUGAUUCCUCUUACCUUUAACGUGAACUCACAGGCGGAUUAAAGUGAAAUAAAACCUACCAUUUGAGUUA